GGCGGGGGCCCGGGGGCUGGGUCCCCGCGGAACUUCCAGAUCGGAAGUGUGGCGGGUCUCUCAGGAACGCAUAUUUUCUUUUCGGAUUCUCCGAGAAGGGGUGGAGAAACAGGAUGGGAACCGGAUUGGUUGCAGUGUGGCACAGACCUGGAACCUUCCUGAAAGAGGUUGGGGCAGGCAGUGACUGUUCAGACGUCCAAUCUCUUUGGGACGCCUCUUCAGCGCUGUCUUCCCUGCCUCUGCCUUUAGGACGAGUCUCAAACACCAACAAACGCAAGGCACGUCCCCCCUCUCAGGUCAGCUGCGAAGGCGUGGGAGCAAGAGAGAGCCUCUCCCUCCUUCUACUUAGAGUUUUUGUUUGUUUGUUUGUUUGUUUGUUUCAAAUAUUAAUGGACGAUAAAACAACACGGAUUUGUCACCUCCUAGCGAAGAGGAAGCCACCGCCACCACACCCCUCAAGCAUGCCUGGGCACUCCUGGGGACAAUCGGACGUGGCAGGAGUUGGCAUGCCCAAGAUGAAGCUGGGAAGGAUGACCCAGAGUGGAAGGCGUGGGCUGGGGCUCCAGGUCUCAGCUCUCGCCAGCGUCGGACCACACAGCUUUGCCAGCUUUGCACCUUGCCUUUCCUUCUUGUGAGGCAUCUGGGACCGUCCUAUCAAGGCGCUUCAAAGGUGGAAGGACAGAGUGCUGGGGACAAGAACGUACCAGGCGCCCAGAAGAUUCCACUAGCGCGGCCAAACACUAAGACCAGGUUUCCUCCCUGCGUGGUGGUCGUUGGUUGUGCACGGGCUACGCACGAAGACUGAAUUCCUGAGAAAUGGAAACUGCAGGAGAAAAAUCAAAUAAACUUAGAGGCCUGUGAAGCUCUCCCUCUUGUCGCUCUGGGACCGCUCUAAGCUGAGCUACAUCUCAGAUACCUUCUCCCCCUGGAGGAUGGGCCUUUCUCAGGCACGAAGUGCGUGUGCCCCACUGGGCUCUUGCCCACAAGAGCAGUCUGAACCCUGGAGAGGCUGACACCGAGGUGUCUUGAAGGAAGCAGGCACACUCUCAUGCUUCCCCACCUAGGGUUUCGCCUUUCUUCUAAUAUUUAGGAUUCCCAGUGAAGGGUACUCCACACACACCCUCUGCCUACCCCUAAUCCCACCCCAUUGUGUCUGAUCCCACAAUUACUCCCAGGGUAUCUAUACUCACAGCUUUUGCGCUCAAAGAACAUUGUCGUCUGCAGGGAACGGGUGGAGCCCUUCUCAGAAGCUCCCGGGGGCGAGUCCAUUUUAAGAAUGAGUUGAAGUAGGAAAGAAAACACAGAUGCUGUCUUUGCAUUCGACAUUCUAUCACCAGCAAGAGAAUAUGUAACUCCUGUUCUUUCCUUCAUUAUUCCAUGAAUUACCUUUUUUCUCUAGGGAUCUACCAGUUGGUGAUUUAGGGCUUUUAAAUAUUAUGCUUGUUAUGUAUUUAACAAAAUGCAAUAUGUCUACUGGUGGCAUUGUUUCCUUGGGAAAUUAGAAAAGUAGAAGCUACAUACUCUAGUUCCUAGGUGGUCUCUGGAAAGUUGGCCUCAUGCUGGUUGGCUAAAUAAUAAGUGUUUAGGAUUUGAAAGGAAGAAAGAGAGCUGAAGUCCUGGUGACAGAGUUUGUGAGAAACAGAAGAUGUAACACUCUGGCAUUUGUUGAGGAGAUGAGGAAGAACUUUUGAAAAAUAAGCUAUUCUAUUCAGUUUUGUGCAAAUUUAUUGCAGUUGCUUCAUAGAGGAAGAAUAAUGUUGAGAAUGGAAUAAUUGCAAAUGCUAGUGAUGAAAUCUAAAGGAAACCUCUACUCAUAGUUAACUGAAAGUAUUUUUGUUGUUGUUGUUUAAAUACUUAUCUCAUUGCUUUCUUUCCUUUGCAGAAUUAUUUUCCUAUAAUAGUUUCCAUUAGGUGUCAGUCUGAACUGGUUCUUACUUAAGUUAGGGGUGAAAAUGUUCCAUCAUCACACCUUUUAAGAUAAGAAAGUGGGAAAAAUUAAAACUUUAUUAAGUUGAAAUUACUGGAGUUAAUUUUUAUUGUUAAAGACAGCUUUUUUAUUCCCAGAAAAAGUAAUUUUAAAUUAUGUCACCACUAGUCAAUGACUGCUUUUGCCCUGUCACUGUCCAUAGCCAUGAUUAAAGAAGUACAAAAUGCUUGUUUGUGCAUUUCAUGCUAGAUCCAAGUAGUGUUAAGUAGUCAUAAUUUUUGGAUGGCUUUUCAAUUGAUGUCCUAAGACUAGAAGGGUAAGCAGCCUUUUCUAAUAUUUCUUUUGCUUUACAAAGGUGAUAGAAAUUUUUCCUGAAAAAAGGAACAUGGAUUCAGCUUAAGCUGUUCAUUUGACAAUACUGAGGGCACAGUAAAGGAGGAGGGAGACAAAUUGUGAAAAUUACUUAUGUCCACUAGUUUUACUUUAAUAAAUCCUGCUUAAAUACUCAGAAUUUAUGAAUACAAUUUAUGAUAUAUAAGUGGGAUAUUUUAGGUCGCCCAUUUAAAUUUAUAUAAUGUCUAUAAAUGGUCAAUUUUAUACUAUAAUAUUCAUUAAUAAGCAUAAGAAACAUCAUCUUGAUUGGUCAUUUGCUACUGAGUCCCAAGUAAGUAGCUUGAUAGAAACUGCAUUUUUCAGAAAAUUUGCUUAUUUUAUUCUUUGUAUUUGUGAAUUCUGUUCUGAUGUUGUUGCUUGAAUAAAAUUGUGGGGAGUGGUGAUGGUAUUCGUGGUUAAAGAUCCAUAGAGCAUUAUGACAACCCCAUGAACUUUCCCUGAGGCCAUUGUGAGCCCUAGAAUGAUGUGGUUCUUGGUGUCAGAGCAAUGCCAAUCUAGAACCAGAACAGAGGUCCCAGUGAAAGUCCAAGCAAAGGCAAGCAACGAUGAAGUAGCAUUUUGAUGGAAGGAAUAUUCCAAAAACCCUAUUAUCAAUUUUUGUCUUAUUAUAUUCCACAUUAGUCAUGAGAAAUUUUCAAAUUUAAAAAUAGACAACAAAAUUAGAGAUGAUGGGUAUAUUGGGAAACAUUUUUGUGUUUUAUGUAAGACAGAGGAGAAGUGCUAAGGACAUAGAAGGAAAGACAGCAUAAGGCCAUCACAGUUGUUCACCAUCUUGUCAAUAUGUACAGGUGCAGCUACCAUUGUAUCACGGAAAUGACAGAAUGAUGUUCUUACUGUGUUGGAAAGUAGUGUAUUCUGCAUGGGAGACUUACUGUUUAAAAGUAAAUUUCUUUUGGAUAUAUUUUCCGUAAGAAGAAAAAAUAUAAUAAUGACAUCAGAAUAUUUAAAGACUUUUAAAUCAUUUAGCUAUUGAAUUUAGUUAUUGAUAGCUGUACAGCUAUAUACACAAAUGGUAAGUAGAGUUUAAGCAAAUAGCUUUGUAGUACAAUUUGUUUUUUAAAUGUUUUCAGAUUUUUAUCUUAGUGCUUAUACUUUAAAUCUUGACUUACAAGUCUUGCAUUUAAGUCUAGAAAACAUUUUGCAUGAUUGUAUAAAAUAAACAUUUUAGUUGAGGAAACACUGCAGUUCAUCCAAAAAACAUAAGCUAAAAAGAUAUAAUAUUUUAAAUUUCUUGAAAUGUGUUUGUUACCCAGUAAUUAGUUGAGUUUGUUGAGUGCAGCCUAACAAUAAAAUCAGUGUAUCUGUAUGUUUGUAUUGUUGACCAGCUUAAAAAUUUAUUACCAACUGUAUCUUGUGAGUUCUGGGUUCUGUUACAUCCUGGCUAAUAAUAAUGUGAGCUAAGCAAGGCAGUCUGAUCUCCAACACAAUUAAAAUAUUAUAAUACAUAUGCAAGGGUAAAGACAACACUUCAUUUGCUUUAUUUGUGGAAAAGCCCUUUGAGACUCAUAGUAUUUGAAAAUAUAUAUAUAUAUAGUAGAUCAAACUAGAACCAAAUGUUAAAAACCUACGAGUUCUAAAACAUGCAGUUCAAAGAUUUUAAAUAAGGGUUAUUGCCUUUAUUAAUUUAAAACCAAUACUGAAUCUCAUUCAGUUAAAUUACAAACUAAAAAAGACAUAUUGCUGGAAUCUAUUAAUACUAUGUUUCCAGUUCAAAUGAAAUUUGUACUAUAAUAUGCUUUUUAAAAAGUUGACAAAUUAUAUUACAAUAGUGACAUAAUUGCAUAAUUUGAAAGUAGGGUCUAUUUGUAAACUUGAAUGAAAUAUGUGCUUUUUGGAAACACUUUUUCUGAAAAGAUUAUUUUUAUAAAAAUGAUACAUUUUAAUUGGAAAGUUGAUAUUUCUUGCAAUUUUGUUUUUAAAAUUUGUAUUCAAUACAUGAGUGAGUAUUAAUUGAAGCCUAUUUUUGUCUCUCUAAGCUAGUGUAGUCAAUUUCAAUAACUGUUUCAAAGAAGUCUCAAGAUAAACUAAAAAUUACUCAUUUAAAAUAGUUUUUUAUAUAUCUGCCAAAUAGUCCAUUAGUUUUUGGAUUCCAAGAAGAAUGAAUGAAUGAAUGAAUGAAUGAAGGUCAUGCCUACUAUUCUGUCAGAAGCAGAUAUAAGAAAAAGACCUUUUCCUUUGUAAUAGAAAUAUAUCAUGAUAAGACUUCCAAAUAUCCUGGAUUGUUUUACAGAUAACUACACAGGAAUUAAAGUUAUAGAAUGAUUACUUUA